GUGGUUUCCGGAACUUCGCCCGCGUCUCUGGGCUUUUGCUCUGUCAGGCUGGUGGCGUUUUGGUGUCUUCGUUUGUUAUGGCCGCUGCUGUCGCUAUGGAGACAGAUGAUGCUGGAAAUCGACUUCGGUUUCAGUUGGAGUUGGAAUUUGUGCAAUGUUUAGCCAACCCAAAUUACCUUAAUUUUCUUGCCCAAAGAGGUUACUUCAAAGACAAAGCUUUUGUUAAUUAUCUUAAAUACUUGCUUUACUGGAAAGACCCAGAAUAUGCCAAGUAUCUAAAGUACCCUCAGUGUUUACACAUGUUAGAGCUGCUCCAAUAUGAACACUUCCGAAAGGAGCUGGUGAAUGCUCAGUGUGCGAAAUUUAUUGAUGAACAGCAGAUUCUACAUUGGCAGCACUAUUCCCGGAAGCGGAUGCGCCUUCAGCAAGCCUUGGCAGAGCAGCAACAGCAAAAUAACACAUCGGGAAAAUGAAAAACUGGAUACAAACGAGGCACUUAAUACAUGUAUAUAAUGUAUUUCUUUUGUACAGUGAAGACAAAAAAAAUGAAAACUCUUCCUAUCUACCUUUAUUAUGGUAGCCCCUAGAACCUUUAGUGUGCUUUUUCAUCCAACUUUUUAUUGUUAAUAGACUAUUUCUGUUAAACCUGAAUUGUUCUUUGAUUUCCCUGUGGAUUUGUAAGGUGUUUUUCUUUUUUACGCAUUUAGCAUAAUCAGCUGAUUAAGAAUGGAAAAGUUAGGUGCUUUAGACCAAAUAAGGCACUGGGGCAUGGGGUAGGGGUGGGCCACCAAGUAUACUGAAUUCUAAGGCUAGCUGUUCCUGACAUAUAGUAGGGCAAGACCAUCUCCUGGAACCUUACUGUCUCAGAUCAACUACUCUACCACUCUACUCUAAGAUGUAGUGAGAGUAGCGGAGUCACUGACCUCUUUAAAUCAUAGGACAGGAACUGCAUAAAGGUUCUUGAAUUCUGCAGGACAGGAAAUAACUGUAUUACCUGCUUUGCAAGGUGGCUUUAAGAAUCACUGAAUCACUGUGGCCUCACUUGACCUAGUCAUGGCAGGACAACUAGUGGUUAGUUACUAACUGGACUCUUGACUUUAGAACAAACAUGAGGAGCCUCAAAUACUUGUGUUCAUUUGGGAAAGCUACCAUUGAUUUGGGAGGUACCACAAACCAGGUGCUAUGUUAAGUGCUUCCUUGAAUUCUCAUUUUAUUCUAAGAACCUUGUUUAUAGAAGAGAAAACUGAGGUUUGGACGGGGUGAGUAACUUGCCUGUGGUUACACAGCUAGUAAGUGGUAGAGUCAGUGUGACUGACUCCCAGCUUGGAGUUCUUCCCAGAACUGGGUUAUAGAGUCUUUCCGGCCGCUCUCCGCCACCUGCCUCAUCCCAAGUAAAGCACAUUGAGACAGCUGCAAAACAAACUGCUUCUAGUGCUCAGGAGUCUGUUUUUUAUUAAACAAAACAAAACUGCCUGAAUUAAGCAGAGGCUAGAUUAGAGGUCAUGUGCUUUCCUUCAGUGGUGAGGUUAGGUUCUACAUUCCAAAAUCAAAGAAGGGGUUUCAGGAAUAUCAUCAGUUGCUUUGCAGAUGGAGAUAACUUAAAAUAAAAGAUACUGAUCUUUUGAGAGA